AGCAAGCCCACAUGGCACAUCUAUACCUAUGUACCAAACCUGCACGUUCUGCACAUGUACCCCAGAACUUAAAGUAUAAUUAAAAAAAAAAAGAAAAGUUUGCUUGUACAGUGAACAGGGCCUGGGGAUCGGAAGCCACCGAAGCCAACCAUUUACGUCAGCUUCUGUGACACGCCUGCAGGGACGGGGCAUGGAGAAUACAGACCUCGCUGACUGGGAUGUUGAAGGACAGGUUUUUAUUCAAACACAGAAGACCCCUAAAGUACUGAACUGUACAUGAGAGUGGGCAAGGAAACUUUACCACUGUCUGAAUAGAAGCCAGCGGAGCUGCUUUCUGUGAAAAGAUGCAAUUGGAAAAGAUGUGGAAAGUAUCUAACACCCAAACCAACCCCACCAGUGUGCCAGCAAUCCUAAGACGCUAUUCUCUAAUUCUGAACGGAAGAACUCCUCUCCCAAGACAUGAGCAUGAAUGCAAUUCCAGGCUGUAAGAUAUUUUGGGAGACUAUUAGAGAGGCAAAUCAACCCACUGGGCUUGGUGCUUUCCACAACUGAGGCCACCUGGUAUUCCCAAAGAGAACAGAAAUUUCGUUCAAGCUUUACGGGAAGCAGAUAAAAAUUAAAAGAUGUGAGGGAUCAGUGCUCCAGGAACAUGGGCCCAUAAAAUUACAAGCUGGAGAAUAACUGCUCCCAGAAAUAUGCUGCAACUACAAAGAAAAACGGACUUUCACUGGCUGACUGAUUGUCUGGAAACCGUUUUGGGAUUUCUUUCCUAAGCUUCUUAAUUAGAAUCUUUACAUUAUAGAGAAAAUGAUUUUGAGAGUUGAGUGUGGUCUGUGGAGUGUCCUAUUAGUAACGACUUCUGAGUAGGUUUAAGUCACCUCUUUUAUUGAAAUGUGAAAAGGUGUGACAUUUAUAAUAGAAAACUCUUUGAAAGUCGCACCGUUCAUUUUAGAGGAAUUUUAAAUGUCACCCCAAAUUUUACGAUUUUAAUUAAUUUUAAUUAAUUUCCAAAUUUUAACCAAUAGGCAUAAUAUUCAAGAUCUUAUCUAAAAAUUAUUACAUGGCAAUAUUUUGUCCUUGUUAAUUAAAAAAUAACACUGAAAACACAGUCGUCUUCCUUUAAGGUAAAAACCUGUCCAAUAGUAACAAUCUCAAUGAUGGCAGAAUGAAAUCAGAAUCUGAUUGGAUUAAAAAGGAGGGAAAGGGUGUGGCUAAGGUGGGUGGAGACACCCUCUGGUAUAAAAGCCCCUGGCAGGCAGCUCUCACUCCAGAUCUGAGCUGUCCGCAGAAGCAGCUGGAGGCCAGGGGAGAAACUCCAGAAGGAGAGACAUUUGCCAUGGCUGAGCACUUCAAACAGAUCAUUAGAUGUCCUGUCUGUCUAAAAGAUCUUGAAGAAGCCGUGCAACUGAAAUGUGGAUAUGCCUGCUGCCUCCAGUGCCUCAAUUCACUCCAGAAGGAGCCCGAUGGGGAAGGUUUACUGUGCCGUUUCUGCUCUGUGGUCUCUCAGAAGGAUGACAUCAAGCCCAAGUACAAGCUGAGGGCGCUGGUUUCCAUCAUCAAGGAACUAGAGCCCAAGCUGAAAUCUGUUCUAACAAUGAACCCAAGGAUGAGGAAGUUUCAAGUGGAUAUGACGUUCGAUGUGGACACAGCCAACAACUAUCUCAUCAUUUCUGAAGACCUGAGGAGUUUCCGAAGUGGGGAUUUGAGCCAGAAUAGGAAGGAGCAAGCUGAGAGGUUCGACACUGCCCUGUGCGUCCUGGGCACCCCUCGCUUCACUUCCGGCCGCCAUUACUGGGAGGUGGACGUGGGCACCAGCCAAGUGUGGGAUGUGGGCGUGUGCAAGGAAUCUGUGAACCGACAGGGGAAGAUUGUGCUUUCUUCAGAACACGGCUUCUUGACUGUGGGUUGCAGAGAAGGAAAGGUCUUUGCUGCCAGCACUGUGCCUAUGACUCCUCUCUGGGUGAGUCCCCAGUUGCACAGAGUGGGGAUUUUCCUGGAUGUAGGUAUGAGGUCCAUUGCCUUUUACAAUGUUAGUGAUGGGUGCCAUAUCUACACAUUCAUCGAGAUUCCUGUUUGCGAGCCCUGGCGUCCAUUUUUUGCUCAUAAACGUGGAAGUCAAGAUGAUCAGAGCAUCCUGAGUAUCUGUUCUGUGAUCAAUCCAUCCGCUGCCAGUGCCCCAGUUUCUUCUGAGGGAAAGUAAAUAAACAUUUGAACAUAAUCAUCUUUAGGAAGUUUCAGUGCUCCCAUAGCCAUAGCUAAGAACUUUUCCGCUAGAUACACAUAGGUACAAAGGGACAGAAGGGAAAGAGCCAUCACUCUGUAAACCAUGAACAGAAAGCAAUUAUAUUAAUGAGGGGAAAAUUACAUUGUACUUAAAGUUUGUCAUGUUGUUUUCUUUGGGGCUUAUGUUUAUAUUUCUGUUCAAUAAAUAUUUUGAAAAUUCAGA